GAUGGGGUGGGGCCCCCAGUUCUUCCCCCUACCAGGCAAACAGACCAAACAGACCUUGCCCGGUUCCCUGGCACAGCUGCACCCCCAACCACCACACACACCCAUGCCCACAAGGUCUUAGCAAGAGGGGGCAUGCCAGAUUGGGUGGGGAUGGGCCGCCUUCAUGGGGCGUCAGGGGACUGGGCCCUCUGGGAUGCAGAGGUGGGAAAGGUGCCCAAGGUAGGGUGGGCACCCUGGCACCAGUGCCCUGCCCUGGCAGAAAGAAGGGGGAGGCCUUUGCCCCACCCAUCCCUCCCAGAUGAUGGGUCUAGGAGGGCCCCUUGGCCUGGUUGGCACCACCAUAGCUCCAGGUGGCACCUAUAUUGGCAUGGGUGUUAGAGCCCUGGGUAAGGGUUAGGGGAGUUUCCCAGAAGCUAGAGAAGCUUAUGAACACCCUCUCCUUCCCACACAUGUCCUCUGCCUCUCCCCCUCUUUCAUUGCUACCUCUUGGCCAUGGGCAUUGGAUUUGGGCCUAAGGAGUUAAACACCCACCCUUGCCCAAUCCCUGUGUGAGUUGCGUGGUGAACGAGCCUGAGCCUGUGACCUGACAGUGAGGUCAGCCAAUCAGCGCCCCCACCACACCAAGUUGCCACGGAGACCGGCCCUGGGGUGGGAGAAAGGAGGCGGGUUUAGCAGCGGGAAUGGGUGGGGUGGGCAGGGAAGGAGGGAGAGGGAUGGGGUGAGCCACGUGCCUGCCAGUGCCCAGCUCCCAGCCAAUGGACAGCGAGGACAGCCCCACCCAUCCCCCUUAGGAGGGACAGGAUCCACUUGGGCCCAGGAGGGUGCCUACUGCUGCUUAAGUAGCUGCAGCCACUGUUGCUGCUGCUCCUCCUGCUGCUGCUGCUGCCCACCUGGUUUUUGUUUGUUCCCAAGUCUGGGGGCCAUUUGCCACUUGUACCAUUUGUAAAGUACAGGCAGGAGGAUUAAAGGGAGCAGGGAGAGCUCCCAGAUGGCUUGGUUCCUAGGGAGAGAAGUGGUUUGCGGACUUACGGUGGGAACAGGAGAAGAUGGGGAGCCCCGAGGAUGACCUGAUUGGGAUUCCAUUCCCGGACCACAGCAGUGAGCUCCUGAGCUGCCUCAAUGAGCAGCGCCAGCUGGGCCACCUAUGUGACCUCACCAUCCGGACGCAGGGCCUUGAAUACCGCACCCACAGGGCUGUGCUAGCUGCCUGUAGCCACUACUUCAAGAAGCUUUUCACUGAGGGCGGUGGCGGAGCUGUCAUGGGGGCCGGGGGUAGCGGGACGGCCACUGGGGGAGCAGGGGCCGGUGUGUGUGAGCUGGACUUUGUAGGGCCAGAGGCACUAGGCGCCCUCCUUGAAUUUGCCUAUACAGCCACACUGACCACCAGCAGCGCCAACAUGCCAGCUGUGCUCCAGGCUGCCCGCCUGCUGGAGAUCCCGUGUGUCAUCGCUGCUUGCAUGGAGAUUCUGCAGGGCAGUGGGCUAGAAGCUCCCAGCCCGGACGAGGAUGACUGUGAGCGAGCCCGCCAGUAUCUGGAGGCCUUUGCCACAGCCACGGCCUCUGGAGUUCCCAAUGGUGAAGACAGUCCUCCACAGGUGCCCCUCCCACCACCUCCGCCACCGCCACCUCGGCCUGUUGCCCGCCGCAGCCGCAAGCCCCGGAAAGCUUUCCUGCAAACCAAGGGGGCCAGAGCAAACCACCUAGUCCCUGAGGUGCCCACAGUGCCCGCCCAUCCCUUGACCUAUGAGGAGGAGGAGGUGGCGGGCAGAGUGGGCAGCAGUGGGGGCAGUGGGCCGGGGGACAGCUACAGCCCUCCCACAGGAACUGCCUCCCCUCCUGAGGGUCCCCAGAGCUACGAACCCUAUGAGGGUGAGGAAGAAGAAGAGGAGCUGGUAUAUCCCCCAGCCUAUGGGCUGGCGCAGGGUGGCGGGCCCCCGCUGUCCCCAGAGGAGCUGGGCUCAGAUGAGGAUGCCAUCGAUCCUGACCUGAUGGCCUACCUAAGCUCCCUGCACCAGGACAACCUGGCACCAGGCCUGGACAGCCAAGACAAGCUGGUGCGCAAACGCCGCUCCCAGAUGCCUCAGGAGUGCCCUGUCUGCCACAAGAUCAUCCAUGGGGCAGGCAAACUGCCUCGCCACAUGAGGACCCACACAGGCGAGAAGCCCUUUGCCUGCGAGGUCUGCGGUGUUCGAUUCACCAGGAACGACAAGCUGAAGAUCCACAUGCGGAAGCACACGGGAGAGCGCCCCUACUCAUGCCCGCACUGCCCAGCCCGCUUCCUGCACAGCUACGACCUCAAGAACCACAUGCACCUGCACACAGGGGACCGGCCCUAUGAGUGCCACCUGUGCCACAAGGCUUUCGCCAAGGAGGACCACCUGCAGCGCCACCUCAAAGGCCAGAACUGCCUGGAGGUGCGCACCCGACGGCGCCGCAAGGACGAUGCACCACCCCACUACCCACCACCCUCUACCGCUGCUGCAUCCCCCGCUGGCCUCGACCUCUCCAAUGGCCACCUGGACACCUUCCGCCUCUCUCUAGCUCGAUUCUGGGAGCAGUCAGCCCCCACUGGGCCCCCGGUCUCUACCCCAGGGCCCCCUGAUGACGAUGAGGAGGAAGGGGCACCCACCACACCCCAGGCUGAAGGUGCCAUGGAGUCCUCUUAAAGAGGGACGAGGGCCAGACUGAAGCAGCACAAGGCCGGGGACACCCAUGCCAAGCAGUGGGAGCACGCAGGACAGACACAGCAGGGGUCUGGGGCACGGAGCCUUGCUGGCAUCAGCAUCAGCCCUUCCUCCCAGAGCCCUCAUUCCAAUUCCAAGCUAAGAAGGUAUUGGGGCAGAGGCUCCCCAAAUUGGGGUGAUCCCCCAAGGAGUGAUACAUAUAUUGUGUAUAUAUUUACAGCUGUAUUGUAAAAGUGGGGUCCCUGUCCCCAGCUGCUCCUGGGGAGUAGAAGCAAUAAUGUAUUUCUAAUUUGUGGGUCCCACUUCGGCUAUGCGGGUUUCUAGGGGGUGGGGGCUUGGGACCAAAGCCUUGCCCCGCCCCUAUGCCCCUUGGGGGUUUUGGCUGUGUAAGGGGGUGAAGGACUGCCCCUCCCUUUCGAGACCCCUCCUUCCUGGUUUCUGUUCCUUUUUCCUGGCAGUGAAUUAUGCAAAGGGGGCCGGCAAAGGAAGGGUAGGUGGGGGAAAGCCAGGUGGAAGCUUGAAAGACUGGGGGACUGGGCCUGUAAGGAAGGAGCCAUCCCAGUCCCCCUCCGCCCUGCUCCCGGCGCUGAGUCAUGGGGUCGUGGAGAAGGGGGCGGGGUGGCCUGAUUGGCUCGCCUGCCCCUGGGGGCAGUAGAGGGGCCCCGCCCAGCUAGGGGAGCCGCUCCGUUCCACUCCCCUCCCUAGCCCUCCCUCCCCACGGCCCUGGGCAGGGAAUGUCUUGUUCCCGCCGCUCCCUCCCCGGGGCCAGAGGGCAGGGCGGGCCGGGCGGCGUCCUACCCUCUUCUCCUCCUCCCCAUCUCCUCCCCGCCCAGGUGCGAGCCGGAGCCGCCGCCACCGCUGCCGCCCCUGACUCACGCCGCCCCCGGGCUGGCGCAGCGAAGGGUGUGGGACAGGGUAAGGGGUUGGAAGAGCCUUGUGGAGAGCGGGCGAGCCGGCGCCAUCUGGCGGCCAUGCUCUGAGUGGGCGAGCGCCCCCCGCGGCCACUGGAGCGAGCUGUCUUCACGCUCCUCAUCCACCCCAGCUGGUGAGCGGCGCCCCCUUGCCAAGGCAGUGGGCACAGAACUUCUCGCUUGGCCGCAGGGGAAGGGGCUGCGGACCUGUGGGAAAGUGAUCCCCUUCCCAGAUCCUUGCCAGCCGGGCUUCCUGUCAGGCAGGGGAGAAUAAUCCCCACUCUGCUCUUAGGAUUGAAUCCACCCCCAUUCUGUACAUAGCCUCUUCUGUUGGUCUUGUUGAAAUCUAGUUUCAGAUUUUUAACUACCCAAUUCUGCUGGGGGUGGGGGACACCCCCCCUUCCUCGCUGGGUGCUGGACCCCUUUUGCAGCCUGGGCUCUGCCUUGCACUAUUUCCCCUUCCUGGCCUGACGGCUCCUCCCCCUCCUUAAAAGGGGCAGGUUCAGGGGCCCGGUGCUCUUCCUCCCUUCCAUGCACCCCCAUGCCCAUUUGCACAGCUGCCCAGGUACCCCUAACAGUGGGGAGGGGUCACAGGGAGGGGGUAGCGGGACCAGUCCCUGUUAUCUAUUUAAAAAGUGAUGAUGUAAUAUAUUGGGGUGGCGGGGAGAUCGGGUUGUCCUGGGCCUCAUCUUAGCAUUUCAGGUGAUGGGGGGAGCCCAGGGCUGGGGAGACCUGGGGCCCAGCCCCAGAAAGUGGGGACAAUGUGGCCUCCCUUCUCCCUACUUUCGGCUUUCCCAGUCAGUGCCUUAGGGGGAGAGGCACUCCCCCCCUCCUAUUCCCUUCCCCCCACCCCAACUCCCCCACCUCGGGUGUAAGCGACAGGAAGAAAUAAUAAUAAUUUAAGAUUCA